GCGGCGGCGGUUGCUGGGUCCCGGCCGGGCUGACUCCGCUUCUGGGCGGCCGGGCCUCCGCGAGUACCGGGUCGACUUCGGAGUCUGCGAGCCCAGCCAGGGGUGCCCGCUUCCCACCCCUCUCCCCGAGCGGCGUCCCCGUCGGGGUCGAACCUCCCCCGCGACAGGCGCCCAGCCGCCUGUUCCCCCAGGCCUUGCCUGCGGACCGCCCUGGGAACGGCGUCUGGGAGCCCCGAGGGGCUGGCGGGACUCGGGGCCCGGGCCAUGCGGCAGCCGCCCCCGCCCCUCCGCGACCAUCCCCGGCCCAAGCGGGAGCCGCAGCGGCGUUUCUGCUCCUCGCUGCGCCGGCGACCCCGGACCCGGCACCCGUGACCCCUCGCGCUGCCUGCGGCCUCGCGCCGAGGCCUGCCCCGGGAGAGACCGUCCAUGCCGUCCAAGGCGGAGAAUCUGCGGCCCUCCGAGCCGGCCCCGCAGCCGCCGGAAGGGAGGACGCUCCAAGGACAGCUUCCCGGCGCUCCGCCGGCCCAGCGCGCGGGGUCCCCACCCGAUGCUCCGGGCUCCGAGAGCCCCGCGCUUGCCUGCAGCACUCCGGCCACGCCCAGCGGCGAGGACCCGCCAGCCCGAGCAGCACCCAUCGCCCCGCGGCCCCCCGCCAGGCCUCGACUGGAGCGAGCCCUGUCCCUGGACGACAAGGGCUGGAGGAGGAGGCGUUUUCGAGGCAGCCAGGAGGACCUGGAAGCCCGGAAUGGGACCAGUCCCUCCAGGGGCUCAGUGCAGAGCGAGGGCCCCGGGGCCCCCGCCCACAGCUGCUCCCCGCCCUGCCUGAGCACCUCCUUGCAGGAAAUCCCCAAGUCCCGCGGGGUCCUGAGCAGUGAGAGAGGGAGCCCGUCCUCGGGGGGUAACCCUCUCUCUGGGGUGGCCAGCAGCUCCCCGAACCUCCCGCACAGAGACGCCGCCGUGGCGGGGAGCUCGCCCAGGCUGCCCAGCCUGCUGCCCCCGCGCCCACCGCCUGCCCUGAGCCUGGACAUCGCCUCCGACUCCCUGAGGACAGCAAACAAGGUCGACUCGGAUCUUGCAGACUACAAGCUCCGCGCGCAGCCGCUCCUGGUGCGGGCCCACAGCAGCCUGGGCCCCGGCCGGCCGCGGAGCCCCCUGGCCUGCGACGACUGUUCCCUUCGCUCGGCCAAAUCCUCCUUCAGCCUCCUGGCGCCCAUCCGCAGCAAGGACGUCCGCAGCAGGAGUUACCUGGAGGGCAGCCUCCUGGCCAGCGGGGCCCUGUUGGGGGCGGAUGAGCUGGCCCGCUACUUCCCAGACCGGAACGUGGCACUCUUCGUGGCCACCUGGAACAUGCAGGGCCAGAAGGAGCUCCCGCCCAGCCUGGACGAGUUCCUGCUCCCAGCCGAGGCCGACUAUGCCCAGGACCUGUAUGUCAUCGGGGUCCAGGAGGGCUGUUCUGACAGGCGGGAGUGGGAGACUCGUCUGCAGGAGACGCUGGGCCCGCACUAUGUGCUGCUGUCCUCGGCGGCCCACGGCGUGCUCUACAUGUCGCUCUUCAUCCGCAGGGACCUCAUCUGGUUCUGCUCAGAGGUGGAGUGCUCCACGGUGACCACACGCAUCGUGUCUCAGAUCAAGACCAAGGGGGCCUUGGGCAUCAGCUUCACCUUUUUUGGCACUUCCUUCCUCUUCAUCACGUCCCACUUCACCUCAGGUGACGGGAAGGUGGCGGAGCGGCUGCUGGACUACACCAGGACUGUACAAGCCCUGGUCCUGCCCAGAAAUGUGCCCGACACCAACCCCUAUCGCUCCAGCGCAGCGGACGUCACCACCCGCUUCGAUGAGGUGUUCUGGUUUGGAGACUUCAACUUCCGCCUGAGUGGCGGGCGCACAGUCGUGGACGCCCUCCUGUGCCAGGGCCUGGUGGUGGACGUGCCGGCGCUGCUGCAGCACGACCAGCUCAUCCGGGAGAUGCGGAAAGGGUCCAUCUUCAAGGGCUUCCAGGAGCCGGACAUCCACUUCCUCCCAUCAUACAAGUUUGACAUCGGGAAGGACACGUACGACAGCACCUCCAAGCAGAGGACGCCCUCAUACACGGACCGCGUCUUGUACAGAAGCCGCCACAAGGGUGACAUCUGUCCUGUGAGCUACUCUUCCUGCCCCGGGAUCAAGACGUCCGACCACCGCCCUGUGUAUGGCCUCUUCCGGGUGAAAGUGAGGCCGGGGCGAGACAACAUUCCGUUGGCAGCUGGCAAAUUUGAUAGAGAACUGUACUUACUAGGAAUUAAAAGACGGAUUUCGAAGGAGAUUCAGAGGCAGCAAGCACUACAGAGUCAGAACUCCAGCACCAUCUGCUCCGUUUCUUGAAGUUUGCUGAACGAGGACUCACAGCUGCAACGUGGGGUGAUUGUAUUGAUCAAAACCCACUGGGAAGGACAAAGAGUUUGCCGCCUUUCGGGGAUCCGAGGGACUGUGGCGACCGUGCCUCUGUGCCAGCGUCCCAGGAAGGAAGCCAACCCUGAGCGAGCCUGUCCUCUGUGGCAGGUCCACACGGUGUGGGUGGGCAGGGCUUGGACCCCCGUCUCCAUGGCAGGUCCAUACAGCAUGGGUGGCAGGGUUUGGACCCGCCCAGCAGCACCACGGACCCCAGCCACUCUCGGGGGCAGACGUCAGAAUCCGUUCCUGAGCAGCUCCUGUGCCCUGGGGGCAGUCACAGAGCCCCCCAACACCCCCGUGCUCUGCACCAGCCUCUCCCUCCACACCCGAAGCAGGCGUCCAUCUGUGUCCUCCUGGCAGCCCCUCAAACACACACCACCCCAUGUCACACGGGUAUCCAGAGCAAGGCUGGAUCUGGGCUAGGUGACCCCUGGGGCCUCAGACCUCUGAGUGGGCCCCAGAGCCCAGCUGAGGAAGCCACACAGCCUCCAGGACGUGGCACGGUUCCCCUCCACUUGGCUGCAAGUCGCCUGCCAUGGGGCGAGGAGGCCUGCACCCCAGUAUAAGGGCCUCCCCAGCUGAGUAAGAAGCUGCUUCCCCUCCUCUCAUAGGCCAAGCCUAUUGUGUGAAACCAUCUCAUGGUCUUGGUGACGUAGACCAUUUUUGAAACCGUCUCAUGGUCUUGGUGACGUAGACCGUUUGCUUCUUUAACUCCAGCCGCGGAAUGACAUUAGUGGAACCGGGCUAGGGAACUGCUGGAAGUUCAGGAUGCCACCACCUUGAACACCUAGGCCAGGGAUCCCCACCAUGUCCCGGGUUUCUUUCUUCGAGAGUAUAGAACCGUUCAUUCUUGCUUUGUGUCCCAUUCCAUCUCUUGAAAAAAUGUAGUCUUUGAAUGUGUGAAAAUCUAGGGACAUUCAAUCUAGUCUUUUAAAUUAUUUUUCCAUAUUUAUAUUUUUAAAUAAAUGCAUAUAUUGAGUCUUAAAA